CCUUUCCUACCUACCUCCAGUCAUCAUUCUAAUUCAGUUCUCUUCUCUUCCCCUUGCUUGUCUCUCUGUCCUGUCCUCUGUUUCUUUCAUACCAUAGUGUCCUCUUAGCACCUUUCUUCCUCACCUGACCUUAAAACAAUCUUUAACAGCCUCUUGCUUACUUUUCCCACAACUAGCUUUCUCUUUUAUCUCCUUUGCUCUCUAUUUCUGCCUAUGACUCUUUCUUGUCAUCUUUUUUCUCUUCCCAGUCUGACUUUGCACAUUGAGGCAUCUCCUUCAGUGUCCUGCGUCUCAGUUUCCUUCCCUCCCACUGUGUGGACCCUGGGAAUUGCUGGAAAGCCAAGCCUUGGACCCUGCCUCCAUGUGCUCCUGUAGGUCAGGGAGGCAGGUGCAGGGCCUGGAUGGAGAGGACAGAGGCUCCCCGUCCCUUUCUGCUUUCCCACCCCAGCUUCUGGUGCCUUUCUCCAUCUCUUGCAGCCUUCUCUGGCCCUGGCCUAGUUUCUGCUCUCUCGCCUCCUUCCCGCUCUGUCUUUUGCUCUCCUUCCUCUUAGCCUCCUAUCUGAACUAAGUCCCUACCUGCCACCUGCCUCCUGUCUCCCCUACCUCCCUUCCCUUGCCCACUAAAGCCAGAUUAAAAUUCAGGUUUUCAGCAGAACCAUCCAUCAGCCCUACCACCCCCUUUCUGCUCCCACCUGUCUGUCAUACCUGCUAUAGCCAACACAUUUAGGCUCCCCAUGCCAUUGUCCUUCCCAUAAAACAUUCUCAGGAGCCCUUGCCAGGGUACAUUUGCAUAGAGCUGUCCUACUAGGUCUGGCGCAGGUGCCCUGAGCUGGAGGUUCAAAUGGGGCAGGUGGGAGUGUUUCCAGCAUCACUUCCAGCCUUUUCCAUGUAGAGCUCAAAGUCCUGUGAGUGGGCCUGGGCUGGCAGGUCGCUUCAGGGAUCUCAGCUGCCUGAUCUCUAUCCUCCUUGCACCACCAUGAGCCCUAAUGGAAGGGAUGUGAGAAACUCUGAUGGGAGCUUCUAAUGGGAAAGGAAAGGAUGGCCUCUCUUCUCCUAUGCCGGAUACCUCAUCUGGGUCCUCAGCCUCUGUCUUAGUGACACACACCCACAGACCUCCCUCCACAUCCCUGCAGGAUGAGGGAGGAAACGCCCCAGGGAGGAAAUGCCAAGAUGGGCCCAGGUACACUAGUUCCUCCCAGCAGUCGGUGCUGAGUCCUUAAGUGUCCUCAAGGUUUGACCGAGGCCCCAGGUCAGCAGGAGGCAGGGUUGCAGUCUGAGGACAUUAGAGAUGGGAAGGCCCUUGGGGGCCAAGUGAAUCUUCUCCUCCCUUUUACAGGCUAAGGAGCCUGAGACCCAAAUAAGUGAAAUGAGCUCUCCAAGUCACACAGCAGGUUGGUGGCAGAGCCAGGACCAGACAAGCCCACGUCUCCUAACUUCUGGCUUAGAGUACUUCUGUCCCUUCCUGGCAGGACUGUGCUGGGCUGAUCCCGCUUGCAUUUUUCAGGGCUCUGUUCCUGCCUCUUGAGGUGACUAAUCCACAGGCCCAGAACAGUAAGCCUUCUUGCCCUGUCACUGUAAGCACCAGCCAGCCCCUCCAGCCAGCCGCUGCAGCUGGCCUCUGUGGUCUGCUCAGAUGCAAGGAAACCAGGCCAGACCAUGGUCACUUGUAAAAUCCCAUCUGGUCCCUGGAAAGAUUCCCCUACGGCUGUCCCUACCAUACCCCCAGCCUUAGAGACGGACAGAAGGGAGGCGGUGGCCAAGCUGCUUGGAUGAGGGAGGAGAGAUUGAUUCUUCUGUCCAUGGCUUUGGCUUCCUGGGAUGAGAAAGGACCAGCAGUGGGAAGGCGGUAAAGGUGGAUUCAGUCUGGGCAUUUGAGGCUCCUACUGUUCAGUGUCUUUUUCACUGCAAACUGUGAAAUGAAGCCAGAGAGCUUUGGUCGGCAGAGACAGGAGGUGAUAAUAGUCCUUAAAUGUUUAGAAACUUGUCUUUGGGGAAUGCCGUUUGUCAUUUCUCUCUCUUCGUCUGAUGUCCAUAUCACCUGACAUCUACGUGUAGUCAUUCCUCUGAGAUUAUCCACUGAGAGCAAGGCAAUGGAGUUUUCUGACCUCUGAUGCCUCAUCUGUCAAAGGAGGGGGUUAAGGGUCUCUAAAGUCAGUCACAUCAAAAUUUGACAUUUUAGGAUUCUAGGCUGGGCUGUGUAUAAGGCAAAAUCAACAGACCCAGACCCCUCAUCCGCAGUAGCUGGGCAGGCACAGAGCUUUACUCUGGGGAGCCUCUGCCUGCCUCCAUGGCCCUUGCCAGGUUUCUUUCUCUGGAUCUGUCCUCACCCUGCCCAGCCCCAGCUCAGCACUCCCCUCCCUUCCUCCCUCCUUCUUGCCUUCUCUUCUCCUCUAUCAGAAGUGCCAAUCUCUCCCUUUCUUCUCUCCUUCGCCCUUCGAUGGCCCAGCCUAGAGAAUUGAAAUCCUCUUUCUCUGAGAGAACCCAAUGUGAGGGGACCUCUCUGGCUGUUGUAUUUUUCAUAGAGCAAGAAGGGAAUGACUGGGGUUGGGGGGAAAAGAGUCCUGCGGGGGUGGGGAGAGCCAAGAUGUGAGAGCAGAGAGGGAGGGAGAGUGGAGUGUGGAGAGAUUUAGUUCCAUCUGAAAGCUGUCGGUGCGAAUCAGAGGCUUCCCUUUGAACCAGCAGCACGAUCUGGAGUGGAGAGCGUGGGGACUGCUCUGGCCCAGGGGGUUCAUUACUGCUCGUUUGAUAAAUCCGGGGAGACAGGGCCUGUCCUCCACCACCCCCUACUUCUGCCGCCUGGUCCCCUGGCAUCUCAUGUGCUUGGCCCCAUUCCCUCUCUGGUUCCGGGCUGGCCUGGCAGCCCAGGCUCUGGGAACAUGACCAUCAGGGCACGUGUGCAGAGACACGGAAGCAGACGGGCAUCCAUGGGUGCAGAGACAAGUACUUGAAUGUGGGAGGGGUGUGUGUGCGCAUGUGCUUGCUGGUAAAUGCAUGCGCUUGUGUGUUAUGGUACAUGUGUCCCUAUAAGAAGUGUAUGACGUACUUGUGUGUGUGUGUGUGUGUGUGUGUGUGUGUGUGUGUGUGUGAAUCUAAGCAUUUCCAGCCCCUCUAGGAUAGAUUUAGAGGUCACUUCCUAGUUCUUUGUCAAAAAUGGGAUUCGACCUUGUUGUCCUCCCGGUCUUUGCAGGAGCAGGAAGUGUGUUCACACACAGAGACUGGCCUAGCUCUGGACCCCAGUGCCCUGAUGAGGAUGGAGCAGGGAGCUGGAGAACAGGGAUAGUCGCCCCAGGAGGAUCAGUGUUAAGAGGGAGAGAGUGCUCCAGGGACCCAGACCCGCUUCAGCCAGGAGCCAGCUGACCAGACGGUGGUGGCUGGACAGCGGGCCGUGCUCCCCUGUGUGCUGCUCAACUACUCUGGAAUUGUGCAAUGGACCAAGGACGGGCUGGCCCUGGGCAUGGGCCAGGGCCUCAAAGCCUGGCCACGGUACCGGGUUGUGGGCUCCGCAGACGCUGGGCAGUACAACCUGGAGAUCACAGAUGCUGAGCUCUCUGACGACGCCUCUUACGAGUGCCAGGCCACGGAGGCCGCCCUGCGCUCUCGGCGGGCCAAACUCACCGUGCUCAUCCCCCCAGAGGACACCAGGAUUGACGGAGGCCCUGUGAUUCUACUGCAGGCAGGCACCCCCCACAACCUCACAUGCCGGGCCUUCAAUGCGAAGCCUGCUGCCACCAUCAUCUGGUUCCGGGACGGGACGCAGCAGGAGGGCGCUGUGGCCAGCACGGAAUUGCUGAAGGAUGGGAAGAGGGAGACCACCGUGAGCCAACUGCUUAUUAACCCCACGGACCUGGACAUAGGGCGUGUCUUCACUUGCCGAAGCAUGAACGAAGCCAUCCCUAGUGGCAAGGAGACUUCCAUCGAGCUGGAUGUGCACCACCCUCCUACAGUGACCCUGUCCAUUGAGCCACAGACGGUGCAGGAGGGUGAGCGUGUUGUCUUUACCUGCCAGGCCACAGCCAACCCCGAGAUCUUGGGCUACAGGUGGGCCAAAGGGGGUUUCUUGAUUGAAGACGCCCACGAGAGUCGCUAUGAGACAAAUGUGGAUUAUUCCUUUUUCACGGAGCCUGUGUCUUGUGAGGUUCACAACAAAGUGGGAAGCACCAAUGUCAGCACUUUAGUAAAUGUCCACUUUGCUCCCCGGAUUGUAGUUGACCCCAAACCCACAACCACAGACAUUGGCUCUGAUGUGACCCUUACCUGUGUCUGGGUUGGGAAUCCCCCCCUCACUCUCACCUGGACCAAAAAGGACUCAAAUAUGGGGCCCAGGCCUCCUGGCUCCCCACCCGAGGCUGCUCUCUCUGCCCAGGUCCUGAGUAACAGCAACCAGCUGCUGCUGAAGUCGGUGACUCAGGCAGACGCUGGCACCUACACCUGCCGGGCCAUCGUGCCUCGAAUCGGAGUGGCUGAGCGGGAGGUGCCGCUCUAUGUGAACGGGCCCCCCAUCAUCUCCAGUGAGGCAGUGCAGUAUGCUGUGAGGGGUGACGGUGGCAAGGUGGAGUGUUUCAUUGGGAGCACACCACCCCCAGACCGCAUAGCAUGGGCCUGGAAGGAGAACUUCUUGGAGGUGGGGACCCUGGAACGCUAUACAGUGGAGAGGACCAACUCAGGCAGUGGGGUGCUAUCCACGCUCACCAUCAACAAUGUCAUGGAGGCCGACUUUCAGACUCACUACAACUGCACCGCCUGGAACAGCUUCGGGCCAGGCACAGCCAUCAUCCAGCUGGAAGAGCGAGAGGUGUUACCUGUGGGCAUCAUAGCUGGGGCCACCAUCGGCGCGAGCAUCCUGCUCAUCUUCUUCUUCAUCGCCUUGGUAUUCUUCCUCUACCGGCGCCGCAAAGGCAGUCGCAAAGACGUGACCCUGAGGAAGCUGGAUAUCAAGGUGGAGACAGUGAACCGAGAGCCACUUACGAUGCAUUCUGACCGGGAGGAUGACACCGCCAGCGUCUCCACAGCAACCCGGGUCAUGAAGGCCAUCUACUCGUCGUUUAAGGAUGAUGUGGAUCUGAAGCAGGACCUGCGCUGCGACACCAUCGACACCCGGGAGGAGUAUGAGAUGAAGGACCCCACCAAUGGCUACUACAACGUGCGUGCCCAUGAAGACCGCCCGUCUUCCAGGGCAGUGCUCUAUGCUGACUACCGUGCCCCUGGCCCUGCCCGCUUCGACGGCCGCCCCUCAUCCCGUCUCUCCCACUCCAGCGGCUAUGCCCAGCUCAACACCUAUAGCCGGGGCCCUGCCUCUGACUAUGGCCCUGAGCCCACACCCCCUGGCCCUGCUGCCCCAGCUGGCACUGACACAACCAGCCAGCUGUCCUACGAGAACUAUGAGAAGUUCAACUCCCAUCCCUUCCCUGGGGCAGCUGGGUACCCCACCUACCGACUGGGCUACCCCCAGGCCCCACCCUCUGGCCUGGAGCGGACCCCAUAUGAGGCGUAUGACCCCAUUGGCAAGUACGCCACAGCCACUCGAUUCUCCUACACCUCCCAGCACUCGGACUACGGCCAGCGAUUCCAGCAGCGCAUGCAGACUCACGUGUAGGGGCCAGAGCCUGGCUGGGGCAUCUCUGCGGGGCAGAGGAGAAGGCUUUCACAGCUGUUCCCUGAUAUUCAGGGGCAUUGCUCAUUGCUCCCUUCUCGGACCAGCCUUCUUCCUCCCACCAUGGCAGGUGGGGAGCAGGUCUCCCAGAAACACCCCGUCCCGAGGAUGGUGCUCUGUGCAUGCCCCAGCCUCCUGGGCCUGCCCUUCCCUCUUCUUCGGGAGGAUGUGUCUCUUCUGACCUGCACUCUUGCCUGACCCUAGAAUGGGGACAGGGAAAGUGAAGGUUAGGGAAAGCAGAGGGGGGCACUUUUUAGCAUUCCCUUUCUAUCCCACCCCUCUGAUCUCCCAUAAGUGGAAAUGGGGGUACCCAGGGAUGGGCAGGCUUUGGCCUAGGGACAUGAAGUAUGGGAGUGGGUGGCUGUGGCACAGACAGGUGGAAAACGGGAUAGCCUGGCCAGUCCCUCUGUUGUCUGCAUUCGUGCCCUGGGUGCCUCUCUCCUUCCUCAGGGUACUGCAGAAGGGAGCGAACAGGGUACUGUUCGCUCUUGUCUACAGAACAGCCCUGGCACUGCAUUCAAAUCCAGUCUUCAUUCAGCUGGGAUCAAAAUGCCAGUCACCUUGGCUACCCACUGUGGACAGCUGUCUGUCAGCAUGCAGAGGGAUCCAGGAAUCCCCCCGGCAGCACGGCCCGCUUUCCUUCUCCUCCAUGCUGGGCCAGCCAGAUAAGUCAGGGUCCUGGUGGAGAAAGAAAGGCUAGGACCAUGUCCUCAUUGACCCAGAUACUGCUGUGUGCUGCACAGCAGUGAACCAACACUAGAGGGAGCCACACAAGCCUCCUCUCCCCAGUCUGCCCCACUUCCUGGCUUUAACUCUUGAGCUGGUUUGGGGAGUGGUGAGGUAGGGGUGGGGGUGCUGUAGGCUCUUUUUCAAAGAAAACAAAAAACAAUGAAAACCUCAUUUGGGAAGAAAAGCUGUAGGGAUUCCCCCACCCAAAUACAAGUCCCAGUGGAAAGGAAAGGUAGUACCUAUUCUUCUCCAUGGGGUUCCUAACACCCUCCAUUACUCUUUCAGUCUCCAAGCACUUUGAAUCCAUUUUUAAACAUUCAGGUUGCCAGACCUGUCACACAGUGGACUCUGAUAGGGUUACGGAGGGGGCCUGGCUCUCAGUCUCUACUCUCCUAUGUCCCAUCAGUUGGUUGGAGGCCACCUUCCAGGGGGUAUGGGAGACAGGUUUUGGUUUUUAAGUGUCUUUUUUUUUUUUCUUGGACCAAUCAGAUUCCUUCUUCCACUUUCAGUGCCUUGAGUGUCAAGCUUUGGAUGACCGACCCUAUGUGGGCGGUUGUGUGGGGAGUGGGUACUUGUGAGCCUCGGACACACUGUUAAGUGUUACAGUGUUAGGAGAGAGAUGGGUGAGGGGACCUGGAGAGGUAAGGGGCCUGGAAAUGGCCCUGACAGAGAACUUGUGCUGACCGGGAGAAGGUGGUGCGGAAGGGCACCGCAGGCAUUACACAGGCCAUUUCUCCUCCUCCAUGUGCACGCACAUCCAACACACACCUUCCAUGUGACUGCUUCUCAGCCACCACUUUCUGACCAAAGAGAACAGGCGCUCCAAGGAGAACCUGUACCCCUGCCCCAGCCUCGCCUUCCUAAAAAGCAGUGUCUGGAGUUGGCUGUUUCCCGCCUCCCCAGCUGCAUGUCCAGCCCAGUGGGAGACAGGGCCUCUGGUGCAGUUCCCAAAAUGUUCCUCGCCCUUUCUCCGUGGUCACCAUUCAUAAUUCAUGUUCGCUUUAAUGAGUUACAUGCUUAUCAGCCACAGGCCAUUACCACCCUUAUGGAUGGGUCUGGGGGGCGACAUUCCUGGCCAACCCCUUGUAGGAAGGACCAGAUAAUACCCAGGAAGCAAGUAGCUCUAAUUUUAACUUCACAGGAAGUCUGUGCAUCCUCCUUCAUUUCAGCAGGGAAAACUCCUGUGGAGUGGGCCCUAUCUGGGGCAUUUACAGGCUUCCAGCUGUAUUCCAUCCCUGGAAGCUGAUACCUUUCUAUAGAGUCCUUUUAUGAGAGCUCAGUGGGAAGGUCUGUCAAGAAAUUCAGGUUCUUGUACAGACAAAUUCAUGCAAAUUUCUAUUAUUUUCACAAAAACCAGAAACCAUGGGGGAAUCCAAAGACUUGAAGUCUAAAGAUGGUGGCUUUUAAAACAUGCAUAUUCCAAAAAGAAUUCAUUUUUGUUUUGGGUUUGGCUAGAUUCUCUUAUUUAUCCCCUUUUAGCUUAAGUAUUAGUUUCAUUCUACUGAAAUGAUGGAGAGAGGGCCUAAGGUUACUAGGUAAUUGAGCUGAUGGUGCAGGGAGAAUUGUUGAGAAAGGAAGCCUAGUUUCCAGAAGCCUGACACAGAGCUACUUCACUGUCCUCUACUCCUUAACAAGGUAACUGGAGCCUCUUGGGUGUCAAACAAGCACCCUGGAAGGCACAGGGAAGCAUCAGCAACCAAGGUAGUCUCUGCCCUCUGUAACUUACGUGUUGGUGCAUCAGAAUCUGAAUUGGAACCUACCUGAUGGGCCCAGUGGAAUAGCUUUUCUGGGGAGUGGAAGGCGUCCUUGAUCACAGAGCUUUGCUGUCGAAUCCUGGAGUCCUGCAACAUGGUGAUGCCUCAGUAGUUGGUGAUCCUGAUCACCUUUGGUGGCUUGUUUUAGUGGAAAGAGCAAGGGACUAAAGGUCAGGAGACCCAGGACCCAGUCCUGAAGCUGCAAAGGUUAGAUCUCGGCCUAACUUUCUGUUCAUUGCCCCCAAUUUGUCUGGCCUGUAAAAUGAAGGGGGAGGGUUGCAUAAACCUAAAACUAUUCUGGUUUUGUUAUACCCAUAGGGUUGGGGGUAGGGAUGGGACUGCCCAUUGCUGGCAAGGAACUGGGAACAGUAGCAAGCAUGGUGAGGGCUGGAGAGCUGGCUGGGGGGGUUCUCUCCUGUUCAAAGAAGCUUUCACCAUGGGCUUCAUUAUCUUGUCAGAAGUGAAUUAGUUUCCACCAGGGACCCCUUUAUCCCAAACAGCAACACAAAAUACACCCUAAACCUCAGAGUAAAAUUGAUGUGGGGCUAUCCUUUGGCUAUCGGGUCAUCUGUGCUGCUCCCCACUCAUUUCUGAUGGGUUUGCAAAGGUGCCUUUUGCCAGGGCAGGACAUAGUAUGCACAUAGGGAUAUUGUUAUGUGCCUAGGUUUCAGGCACUCCUUCUGUAGGGGAAAAUGGGAGGAGCCUUCCUCCACCCUGAUCCUUAGGAACAUUCCUCUGGCCCAGGGACAGCUUGUUCUUCUCACCAAACAGGUGAAGCCUGCAGUCCAAGGUGCCUGGAGCCAGAGGUCGGGGAGUAAGCACAGCUGCCCCUGCCUGAGAAGGAGCAGCUUGCAAGGGGAGCCGGUGGAGGGAAAGGGGUACAACAGCUUUGGAAUACAUUCUGGAUCUUGAGGAGGAUCUUGUGAUUUUGGCUGAGCCACGGUCACUUCCCUCGUGAAGGACCCGCCCUAUAUCCUAAAUUCUGGAUCCCUCAAAGUCCAGCCACAGAGUUUGCAUGAAGCAAAAAGCCUAGUAAGUGAGAAAGGAAAGGGGCCAGGGAUGGGAGCAGUGCUGUGCUGUUAUCACUGUCUUGCUUGGAAUGAAAACAUCUGAGCACCCUGUCUUCAAGCGGUACGCUCUCCCCUUAUUCCAGCAGGGCUACUUUCCUCUUCACUCUGAUGAGGGGAGCUUUAUCUGCUUUCAAAAUGGAGCACGUCGCACUGGAGUUUCGUGCCCUCUCGUUAACCUGUCAGGAGCCACAGGGCUCCAUAAAACGGAAUCAGUGUCUCAAUAUACAUGACCUAUGUUCAUAGCAAUGUUCAGCCAUUUGGGUUUGAAGAAAACCACAUUAAAGCCAAGACCCGUUUGGAGCGAACUGCCUUGUUCUUUGCUGUGUGGAAGGUUCUGUCCCUACUGCUGAACUCCAGUUCCUCCCCAAGCACCCUGGCCUCAGAAAUCCUGGCUUCCCCAAGUUAGUGCUGUCUGACCUGAGCCAGGCCACUGCUUGGUGCCUCUACAGGCCACUGUGCAUGUUGAGAAUUGCCCAAAAGGAUUAGUGAAGCUCCUGACCCUGGCGAGGCCAUAAUGAACACUGAAGUGCACAGGCCAAGGGAUGUAAUUGAAAGGCAUUUAUUUUUGUGAAGAUGCUGUAAAAUUAGCAUUUAAAUAUCCCAUUCCCUUCUCUUGGCCUCCUCCUAUCCCCCUAUGGUAUUUCUCCUCCUCUCCUCAAGGCCAGGCUUUUUGUGAAAGGCAUUGGCUCAUCUUUGUCAGCGUGGUCCUGACGUUCACCUCUGGGCUGCUGGAGAGGACUGAGAGAUGUGUGGUUUGGUAGGAAGGGGGUGUGUGUGGGGGUUAGUGGGGAAUCCCAUUUUUUUGCAUCACUGUGAGGUAGCUUCAGGCCCUGUCCCUGGAGAAAUAAUUGCUGCGCAGAAGUCACAGGCCAUACUGGGCAGUUCUGGUACAAACCUGCCCUUAUUAAUAAUAACAAUAAUAAUAAUAACUCCAUUUGCAUAGAACUGUCACUCAUUCCUGCCAGUCUGCUGUCCCUACCCUGGUUUUUUGCUGGCCCCAACCACUGGCCUUGUUGAGUAUCGAUGGGCCCUGAGCUCUUCUGUUUGCUUUUGGAGCUCUUCAGAUGCUGUCCCCCCUGAGAAUACCCUAACUCUGGGGAAAGAGCAGCCAAAAUCCCAAUACAGUAAAACUCCACACAAUCUUGUUAGCAACAGUGACCCAGAAAAUUUUGAGAAGUCCAAUUUCACCAGAAGAGGCCCAGGGCUCCCUGUGGUCACAUUUUCUACCCAGCCAUUCUUGGCAUUGCAACCUCCAUUUCUAGCUCCUGUUGAAUUUUCUCCACCCAGACCCCAAAAAUAAAUGGAUCCAUGAUGAUAAUUAAGAGAAGAGAAAAAAAGAUAUUAUUUUUGUUAGGACAAACCAUUGUAGGUUUUUAGCAAUGUGUAUCUGUGUGUCCCUCACACCUUUUCCUAUUCUACUUUUUUUUCCUUUUUUUAAAAAUAUUAUGUACUAUAUUUUUAGUCUCAAACACACUAUAUAUUAUAUAUAUUUAAUUUUUUUAUAUAUAUAAAUAUAAAUGUUUUAAAAAGUA